GGAACCGAGCCCAGGAGCCGGGGACGGUGCGCCAGUGCCCCCUCCGCGAGCCCCAACCAGUAGACGGUUCCCUGUCUCCCGCGCCCCAAUUUCGAUUUUCAAACGCAACUCCUACAGGAUUCUGAGACCCCGUCCCAUCUCCCAUAUCCCAUUUCCAGCUGCAAAUUACUGCAGAAUCUGAACCCAGGAAAGAAACCCAUUUGCCGACCCCCUCUUCCCUCUCCAGACAGGUGGAGAGCGGGUGAGGGUCUCGCUCGGCUUUCCCCCUGCACCUUUCCCACCCUCCCGCCCGUCCCUGGGGGUCCUCCGUCACCGCGGCCAUGGCCCAGAAGCCGAAGGUGGACCCCCACGUCGGGCGGCUGGGAUACCUGCAGGCGCUGGUCACGGAAUUCCAGGAGACCCAAAGCCAAGACGCCAAGGAGCAAGUCCUCGCCAACCUCGCCAACUUCGCUUAUGACCCCAGCAACUACGAGUAUCUGCGGCAGCUGCAGGUCCUGGAUUUAUUUCUCGAUUCGCUGUCGGAGGAGAAUGAGACCCUGGUGGAGUUUGCUAUUGGAGGCCUGUGCAACCUGUGCCCAGACAGGGCCAACAAGGAGCACAUCCUGCACGCAGGAGGUGUCCCACUCAUCAUCAACUGCCUAUCCAGCCCCAAUGAGGAGACGGUGCUGUCUGCCAUCACCACGCUCAUGCACCUGAGCCCGCCGGGCCGCAGCUUUCUCCCAGAGCUGACCGCCACGCCCGUGGUGCAGUGCAUGCUUCGCUUCUCCCUCUCGGCCAGCGCCAGGCUCCGGAACCUGGCACAGAUCUUCCUGGAGGACUUCUGCUCCCCCCGCCAGGUGGCCGAGGCCCGCAGCCGGCAGGCGCACUCUGCCCUGGGUAUCCCACUGCCGAGGAGCGUGGCCCCACGGCAGCGCUGAUCCAUGGAGACUGCGAGACCGUGGCACCCCUACUGCUGGAGACCACAGUCCUGAUGUGGACGCAGGGAACGGGGAGCACAUACUGCCCCAUUGGUGCCUUUUCAGCCAUCUGAAAGGCGGGUUCUUUCAGCAGGACAGGCAUUUACACUGAUGAAACGCCACUGGGAGUGAGGAAGCCAGACUCCAGAGACACGGAGAAGAUCAAACUGGAGCUGCGUUCAUAGGCUGGCACUCUCAAUCCUACAUCAGGUGCCACCACCACCAGACUCAGGCCCUGGUGUAAGAAGCGGCCAAGUGCCUGGACCCAGAGGCUUUGCAGGACAGUGUUCUCAGGAGCUGGGCCUGAGGCUUAGGAGAGCUGCCUUCGCUGCAGGAAAUCAGGGAUUAUCCCUUAACAGAAGUGUCUGGAGUAGUUUUCAGGUAUAGGAAUGAGAUGCCUCGUGGUGAAAGGAUCUCACCCUGGGAAGAUGUGGUGCCCCCUCCAGGGCUCUGGAGGAUGGAUGCCUCCCCCAGGGGCUCUCCAAGCUGGGCAUUUGGGCCUGGUGGAUGCCAACCUGGAUAACCUGUGGCCCAGCAUUGACUGUCCACCCAGCCUUGCUGUUAGGCACCAUGACUCCAAGAUGAAGAUGUGGUCCCUGCCCUUGAGUGACAGCCCAGGGACUUAAUGUGGCCAUCGGGCAUCAAGCACAAGGCCAUGCAGGUGAUGAUACGUCGGAAUAGAGGCACCAGCCCUGGUAACUGCAUCUUCUCCCCUUGCCACCCCAUGGCCCCGGCUGAAAGCUUCGGCCCUCCUCUGCUGUCACUCAAUGAUGGGGAGCCCUACCCCAGAAGUGUAUCCCACGAGGGCAUCAGGGACGCAGUGAGUGUUGCUCAAGGGAGUCAGGAAGAGACGGCAACGUAAAGGAUGUGGCUCCAUGUCCAUGGUGCCCCCUGGUCAACAUAAGGAGCGUGGGAUCCGAUGGAAAGGUGGAGCUCAGGGAAAAUGGGGGUCCUUGCCUCUCGUGUACCCCCUCAAGGCUGACCCCUUAGAUGGCCCAGGAAUGGCAGGUGCUACAAAAAUGGUACCCACGUGGGCAUGGAAAUGGGGCAGAUUAGGGGACCACUGGACUCAGAGGGGAGGGAAGGGCUCAUCAGCACCCGCUCAGGGAGCCUGUCCCUUUAUGUUCCCAAAUAAAGGGUCCUAGAAGACUAGAAAGCCAAGGUCUUUUAUUAAAGGUCCCGACUGGUUUUCCCA